AGCCCGCCACCCAACUCGGGCCGCACCAGGGGCCGCACCUGCCCGCGCGCACACGCCCCCCGCGCGCCAGGCCUCGCCGCCGCCGCCGCCCUCGGCACGCGCCCGCUGCGGCUGCCCCCCACCGCCCUGCCUCGGCGCGGGCCACAGCGCACGAGCCGCCGCCGCCGCCGCCGCGCUCCUCCCCGCCGCGGACGCCGCCCCCGCGUAACCGCCGAGGAAGCCGAGGCGAGCCCGGGUCGGGCGCGAGGGCGCGCGGGCCGCUGCUGCCACCGCGGGUGUUCCCUGCGCUCCCGCUCCAGCUAGGACUCUCUCUGCCGCCUCCUCCUCCUCCUCCGACCUCAGUCCUCACCACCCUCCUCCCGCUCCUCAAAAGCACCCCCGAGUCCCCACCCCCUCACGCCGCACCCGCGGGAACGAGGCCUUGGGAAUUCAGGGGAGUGGCUGUGGGGGCGCGUCGCGGCUCCCAGCUCGGCCAGCCCCUCUUUCAAGACAUGGUCUGAUCCCCAUUGUAAAAGCUGCGCCCCGAAGAGGAGGAGAGAGUCGUGCUCCCUGCCUGGGGCUGCAGGGAGCUCUCCGUGCUGAAGCUCUUGCAUUAUUUUAGGGUGGGGCGAAGAGGGCCCUGGAUUUUGGGGAGUGGGGGUGGGUGGGGAGGAGGACCCGAGGGGGGCAAGGACUCUGUGGGGGAGUCGGUGAGAGACUAUGGGGAAGGACCAGGAGCUGCUGGAAGCUGCUCGCACUGGAAAUGUGGCUCUGGUGGAGAAACUCCUGUCUGGCAGGAAAGGAGGGAUCCUGGGCGGUGGAUCCGGACCCCUGCCCCUGUCUAAUCUGCUAAGCAUCUGGCGAGGCCCCAAUGUGAACUGCACAGACAGUUCGGGUUACACUGCUUUACACCACGCAGCCUUAAAUGGACAUAAGGACAUAGUUCUCAAACUACUUCAGUAUGAGGCAUCAACAAAUGUAGCAGACAACAAAGGGUAUUUUCCUAUUCACCUGGCUGCCUGGAAAGGAGAUGUGGAAAUUGUGAAGAUUCUUAUUCAUCAUGGACCAUCACAUUCCAGGGUCAAUGAACAGAACAAUGAAAAUGAAACUGCCCUACACUGUGCAGCUCAAUAUGGACACUCAGAAGUAGUUGCUGUUCUCCUAGAAGAGCUCACUGACCCGACAAUUAGAAAUAGCAAGCUGGAAACACCUUUGGACUUGGCGGCACUCUACGGACGGCUUAGAGUGGUAAAAAUGAUCAUCAGUGCACAUCCUAACUUAAUGAGCUGCAACACUCGCAAGCACACGCCACUUCACCUUGCUGCGCGCAAUGGCCACAAAGCAGUCGUGCAGGUGCUGCUGGAGGCAGGAAUGGAUGUGAGCUGUCAAACAGAAAAGGGGAGUGCACUUCAUGAAGCAGCUUUGUUUGGAAAGGUGGAUGUUGUACGAGUUCUGUUAGAAACAGGAAUUGAUGCCAACAUAAAGGAUAGCUUAGGUAGAACUGUCUUGGACAUUCUGAAAGAACAUCCAUCUCAGAAAUCUCUCCAGAUUGCAACACUCUUACAAGAGUAUUUAGAAGGCGUGGGAAGAUCUACAGUCCUCGAAGAGCCUGUACAGGAAGAUGCAACACAAGAAACACACAUUUCAUCUCCUGUUGAGUCUCCUUCCCAAAAGACCAAAAGUGAAACCGUCACUGGAGAAUUAUCAAAACUCUUGGAUGAAAUAAAACUCUGUCAAGAAAAGGAUUAUUCGUUUGAAGACUUGUGCCACACAAUAUCAGACCACUACUUAGAUAAUUUGAGCAAGAUUUCAGAGGAAGAACUUGGGAAAAAUGGAAGCCAGAGUGUAAGAACCUCAUCUACAAUCAAUUUGUCACCAGGAGAAGUGGAAGAAGAGGAUGAUGAUGAAAAUACGUGUGGGCCAUCAGGACUUUGGGAAGCAUUAACUCCGUGUAAUGGAUGUAGGAACCUUGGCUUCCCCAUGCUUGCCCAGGAGUCCUAUCCAAAGAAGAGAAAUUACACUAUGGAAAUUGUACCAUCUGCUUCUCUGGAUACAUUUCCUUCAGAAAAUGAGAACUUUCUGUGUGAUCUCAUGGACACAGCUGUUACAAAGAAACCUUGCUCCUUAGAAAUUGCAAGGGCACCUUCCCCAAGAACUGAUAAUGCCUCUGAGGUAGCAGUUACUACUCCAGGAACUAGUAACCAUAGAAACAGCUCAACAGGCCCAACACCUGAUUGUUCACCUCCAUCCCCUGAUACUGCCCUCAAAAAUAUUGUAAAAGUCAUUCGACCCCAGCCUAAACAGCGAACAUCCAUUGUGUCUUCUCUGGAUUUUCACCGAAUGAAUCACAACCAAGAAUAUUUUGAAAUCAACACAUCUACAGGGUGCACAAGCUUUACUGCCAGUCCUCCUGCUAGUCCACCCACCUCUUCUGUGGGAACCACAGAAGUCAAGAAUGAGGGAACUAACCAUACAGAUGACCUCUCCCGACAGGAUGACAAUGAUCCCCCAAAAGAAUAUGAUCCUGGGCAAUUUGCAGGCCUGCUCCAUGGAUCCUCUCCAGCCUGUGAGUCCCCUGAAAAUCCAUUUCAUCUCUAUGGGAAAAGAGAACAAUGUGAAAAAGGACAAGAUGAAGUCAGUUUGGCAAACAGUCCUUUGCCUUUCAAGCAGUCUCCAAUAGAAAAUAACUCAGAACCUUUGGUAAAGAAAAUUAAACCCAAAGUGGUCAGUAGAACAAUUUUUCACAAAAAAAGCAACCAACUCGAAAACCAUACCAUUGUUGGCACAAGAUCAACCAGGAGUGGAUCUCGGAAUGGGGACCAGUGGGUUAUGAACGCAGGGGGAUUUGUGGAGAGAGCCUGUACUCUGGGGAGAAUAAGGUCAUUGCCUAAAGCCUUGAUCGACAUGCAUUUGUCAAAAAGUGUCUCUAAAUCUGAUUCUGAUCUCAUUGCCUAUCCUUCCAAUGAGAAAACAUCAAGAGUUAACUGGAGUGAAUCUUCCACUGCUGAACACAGUUCUAAAGGGAAUUCUGAAAGAACACCAUCCUUCACAUCGGAAUGGGAAGAAAUUGACAAAAUAAUGAGUUCCAUAGAUGUUGGAAUCAACAACGAACUUAAAGAGAUGAAUGGUGAGACCACAAGACCCAGAUGCCCUGUCCAAACAGUGGGACAAUGGUUGGAAAGCAUUGGGCUACCUCAGUACGAGAACCACCUGAUGGCUAAUGGAUUUGACAAUGUGCAGUUUAUGGGAAGCAAUGUUAUGGAAGAUCAGGAUUUGUUGGAAAUUGGAAUCCUUAAUUCUGGGCACAGACAAAGAAUUCUACAGGCAAUCCAGCUCCUUCCAAAGAUGAGACCCAUUGGGCAUGAUGGCUACCAUCCCACCUCUGUAGCUGAGUGGCUGGAUUCCAUUGAACUGGGCGACUACACCAAAGCCUUUCUAAUUAAUGGCUACACUUCGAUGGACCUGUUGAAAAAAAUCUGGGAGGUUGAACUUAUUAAUAAAAUCACUCUGGGAGCUAUGUGAAGGAUCGAUUGGAGACUGGGAAACCAGGUAGGAGAAGAUUUACAUAUAAUCCAGGUGAGAGACAAUGAGAGCAUAAAUCCAAAAAAGCAGCAGUGAAGACGGAGGGGGGAGAUGGGUUCUAGAGAUGGUUUGGAAGUGGGGUUGGUAAGAUUUGGUGACCAAUUAGAUAUGGAGAUGAGGAAAUGGAAGGAAUGAAGUGUGACUGCCAGCUUACAUGCCUAGUGGUGCCCACUCACCACAGUCACAAAGAGGGAGACCAGGCUUGGGAUAAAGAGAGUGCGUUCCAUUUUAGACAUGGUGUGGCUCUAGAGAACAUUUAAGGGAAGAUGGCCAGCACAUUGUCAGAUCUCUAGGCCUGGAAUUCAGGCAGACCUGGGCCUUGGUCAGAAGAGUCUGAUUUCCAAUGUCACAUCCCAAAGUGCUUCACAUUAUGAGGAAGUAGACAAAAAGUUGAUUUAUGUUUAAGGGAGUUAAACACUUGAUUAAGAUCCUGGUUAUUCGUUCAUUCCACCAAUAUUCAACUGCCUCCUCAAUAUCUCCACUUGUCUAAAAGAUAUGUCAAACUCAACAUUGCCAAAGCUAAGUUCCUAAUCUUCCCUAAAAAAGACUUCUCCACCGCAGCCUUCCCCCAUCUCACUUGAUGGCAGCUGCAUCUUUCUAGUUGCUUAGGCCAAAAAUCUUAAAUGCCUGGAUCCUGGAUGCCUCUCUGUCUCUCAUAUGCCAAAUUCAAUCUUUCAGCAAAUCCUGUUGGCUGUACUCUCGGAAUAUAUGCAGAAUGUAACUGCCUCUCACCUCUUCCACGGCUGCCUCCCUGGUCUAAGCCACCACCAUCUCCUGUCUGUAUUAUUGCAGUGGCCUUCUAAUUCGUCUUCCCACCUCCACCUUGUCCCCCUUCUGGCUUUUCUCAAUAUUGCAGCCAGAGAGAUCCUAUUGAGAUGUAAUAUCUGACCUCAUCUCUCCUGUCAUUCUCCUGCAAGCUCCUUCUACUUCAAACCCAAAAGACCGUUCUUACUCUUCCCUGUUCAUGCCCACCUCAGCCCUGUACCUGCUGUUCCACUCUCUGGGAAGGUCUUCCCUCAGAUAGCUACAUAAUUUACCUCCUUCAAGUCUUUUCUUAAAUUAUGUUCUCAAAGGUGGUCUUCUCUGGCUUUUUAUUUUAAAGUAUACCUCCCCAAUUCCAAGCCCUCUUCUCUAAUCUUUUUCUGCAGUACUUAUCGUCCUCUAAGUAUAAAUUCCUCUUAUGAUUUUGUUUAUCUUUUUGCUCCACUGGAAUGCAAGUUCCAUAAAGAGAAGGACAUUCAUUUUAAUGCGUGAUUUAUCCCCAGCAUAUAUAAUAGCACUAGAAUAGAAUAUUCUAUUCUAUAGAUACAAUAUAUCAAUAUUUGAUCUCAAUCACUCAACAAACACUUAAAGGAUGAAAGGCAGGAAUAAAGAAAUGGAGGGUGGGCAGGAGGGAGGGAGGGAGGGAAGGAACUGAAGCUCUAUGUCCUGAGCAUUAUCGAGUAUAUACAAAAUUAUAUAAUAUAUGUCCUUGCCCCUCUUUUAGUCUGUUGACAGAAUAAGACACAUUUCCAUGAAGAAAGUUAAGUAGCAGUAUGAGUGCAUGCUGGAGUCAUCUAUAACACUUGUAGUCUUAGAGCUUUUAAGAACCUAGGCUAGUGGAAGAAUAUAGUGACAUCAUCUGUUCUCAUAUUUCUCUCUGGUUAACUAAUGGACAACAUUGCCACAAAGCAGGCAUUUCUCUACUAAGCUUAGCAAAACCUCAUAUGUUUUUCAGACACAAAAUGCAAUUGUGAAAUUACAUGUACCAUCAAGCUACAUAAACACCAUUUUGUUCUACAGUCAUUUACCUUAGCACUCCUAUUGGUUUGCUGACCUUGUUCCAUUUGCAAGGGAGGAGCCCUAAUGGCUCAAUCGCAUCCUAAAGGCUUCACUUCUUAACAGUAUCUCAUUGGCAAUACCUGAAUUUUGAAGAGGUUACAUUCAAACUAUAGCAGCUCAUGCUCACUUUCUAGGAGUCUUGGGAGUUUUUUCCUCCUUUAAAUAGAAAAAGAAAGAGAAGGACACUAAAAUCUAUUUAGUAAGCACCUACUUUACCAUGAAAUUGUGUUUCAGAGAUACUAAAGAAAAAUAAAACAGGUUCGCAGAUUUCAAGGAUCUUGAGGAGUGCAGAUAAGUACAUAAGUUGGUGUUUGGAUUGAGUAUUAUCUAAGUAUCUAAAUGGGACAGACAAGUGUUUCAUGCAUCACUUCAAGGAUCAUGCUAAAAUGCAGAUUUGAAUUCAGCAGGUCUGAGGCAGAGCCCCAAGAUUCAUUUCUAACCAUCUUCCAGGUGGUGACAAUGCUGCUGCUCAUUUAAUGACACUUUGAGCAGCAAAGAUGUAGACAACAAGGGCCAAGAACUUCAGAAUAUGGAUUUAAAUAAUUAGGAAUGGUCAUAUCAAAAAGAUGAGACAUGAGCUGGACCUUGAAGAUGAGAAGUAUCCAAAGGAGUAAACUGGAAAAUAAAAGAACUAAACUGAGGACCAAAGCAAGGCCAUGUAAGAUGCAUUCCAGGACAGUCAACAGAAGAAUUGGAAAAAAAAUUACCAGAGGCAAGUAUUAGACUAGAAAGUUGGAAAGAUCAACUGGAGUCAGCUUGUGGGAGGUUUUGUAUGCCAGGUUGAAGACUAUGGAUUUCAUCCUGUAACAAAAUGAACACCAGUGAAAUUUAAGGAAGAGGAAGAGAAGACCUAGAUCACAAUGUGGUAAUGAAAAUAGAAAGAAAGGAAUGUGCAUGAGGUGGAGGGCUCUAGAGAAAGAGGUAAUCCUUGGCAAAAAAAAAAAAAAAAAAAAAAAAAAAAACCACUCUAGAUUCUCAAAUGGACAUGAUAAACAUUUUGAAGGAAGUAUCAAUAAGACAAAGCCAAUUAAAAAGCUGAAAAUAACAGGCCAGGCAUAGUGGCUCAUUUCUGUAAUUUCAGCAUUUUGGGAGGCCAAGACAGGAGGAUCACUUGAAGCUAGGAGUUCAAGACCAGCCUGGUCAACAUAAGACCCCAUUUCUACAAAAAUUUAAAAAUUAGGCCUAGCGCAGUGGCUCACACCUGUAGUCCCAGCACUUUGGGAGGCCAAGGUGGGUGGAUCACUUGAGAUCAGGAGUUCAAGACCAGCCUGGCCAACAUGGUGAAACCCCAUCUCUACUACAAAUACAAAAAUUAGUUGUGUGUGGUAGCAGGUACCUCUAAUCCCAGCUACUCAGGAGGCUGAGGCAGGAGAAUCGUUUGAACUCAGGAGGCAGAGGUUGCAGUGAGCCAAGAUCACAGCACUGCACUCCAGCCUGGGCAACAGAGUGAGAUUCUGUCUCAAAAAAAAAAAAAAUAGCUGAGUGCAGAGAUGUGUGCUUGUAGUCCUAGCUACUUGGGAGGCUGAGGCAGGAGGAUCACUUGAGCCCCGGAGUUUGAAACUAUAGUGAGCCAUGAUCGCACCACUUCACUCCAGCAUGGGCAGUGGGAUGAGAAGCUGUCUCUUAAAAAAAUAAAGGAAGUUAAAGAUAACAAUGAUUUUGAACUUGGAUGACUAGGAGAAUUAUGGUAGAAAAAUGUAGAUUGAGAAAGGAGUAAGUUUGUUCAGAGAGCAGAUGAUGAGUUUGGAUUUAGAUAUCUGGAUUUUGAAGUGAUGGCAGAAUUCUAAGUGGAAACUUCUGGUAAACCACAAGAGAUGUGAGGUGGAGAGCAGGCAGGGGUCAUCACCAUAGGCAAAGACGUUAGGUAAGUCAGCAGAGUGAUGAUCAUUGAAACCACGAGGCAGGUAUUGAUCGCCGAGGGUCCUGGAUACUGGAGAAGGUCACAGACAGACAGGGCUGAGGAUCAGACCUACAGACGUGUCCUUAUUUAGGGAACAGAGAGAGAGGAGCCUGCAUGCCAAAAGGUGAAAAGAGAAAAUUUCAAAUACUUCAUUAUCUGUGAUGCUUUCACUAAAACAAACUUUUUGACCCACAGGAUUUGACAAUGUGUAAGCACAUUUGUAUUCCAUCCUUAGUGCAGUCAAUGCUACGCUCUGCUAACGUGGCCCCAGGAGGCCAAGGUUCCAGUGCCAGUUUUGUUACCUGCCUGCUCUGUGGCCUUGAAUGACCCACUUUAACCUCUCACCUCAGUGAAAUCACCAUCCAAAAGACGGGGGGAAUACUACACUACUACAAGUCUCACAAAGAUGUUAUGAAAAAUGAAAUCAUAAAUAAUUUUAAAGCCCACAUUUUAAUGAAGCCAUCAGAUGACUUUUCUAAUUUAUCAAGAGUUGAAUGCAGUUUAUAUGCAGUUCUCGUGCAACUGCCCAACUUAGAUUACCAGGAAAAAAGGCAAACAGAUUUAUUUUUCUGAAUUAAAAUAGCCCUAUCUAGGUUUUUAAAUACAUUCACCAGAUUUUAUUGAGGGCUUUUUGUAUGCUAGGUACUGUGACAGGCAAUUGACCAGAUACACAGUUAAAUCAACAAAGGCCCUGUGAUGAAAGGUCUUGGAAUCUAAUAAGAAAAAAGAGAAACACAAAUCAUGCAUAAUCAAACAAAAAUCAAUAUGUAACAAAUGCCAUAAGACCCGUAUGAACCAAGUACAAUUGAUGUUCACAGAAGAGGAAAUUUCUGGCUGACGGAGAGAUGGGAUGAAGGCCUUGAACAAGGGUACACGGUGACAGAUGGAGAGGAGAGGGAGGGCAUCCCCUGUAGGCCCAGAGGGAAGAGGGCACAGACAGGGCUUGGGCAAUGGCGAGGAGCACAGUUAGCUUGGAACAUGGAACAAUUAGGAGAGCAGCAGGAGGUAGUCAGAUUGCAAAGGGCACAGAUGCCAGGCUACCGAGUCAGGGCUAUAUUCUGUGGACAGCAGAACACCGGGAGGGCAACAAAGGACCCAGACAAGCAAAGGACUUCAACUGGAGCUGUGCUGAAGAUGGUUUAGCAAAGAGAUCGGCUUCUGGGAGAAAAGAGACACAAUAGAAUAUUGGUGACGUGGAUGAAUUUUUUUGUUUCUCAUUAAAAUGGGGACAGCAGUGUUCUAUGAAAACUGUCACAGGCAUAUUCUUCCAAAGGAAAUUAAUUUUAAUAGAAACAUAGAAGUGAUCCCCUCUCUUUCCAAAGUUUCACGCUAUGUCUCAUAGUUAAUGUAAAGUUUCAAAGUCAAAGACAAAUGUACUGUCCACUAAAGCCAGGAAGACUGGCCAGGAUAAAAAGCUGUGAACCAGCUCCAGGGGUCAGGGCAGAAAGGAGAUAAAUAGAACAGUUGGAGCAAUUGUUCUAAACCCUUUGGAAACCACAGAUUCCUUUGAGACUCUUCACAUAGCUCAUAUAUAUGUGAAAUUCUGCAUGUAAUUUCAGGGGGGUUGUAGAUCCCCUGGGCCCUAUUCAUUGAGCCCCAGAAACUCAAAUUAAGAAUCUCCGAGCUGGAAAAGAAAAAAAUAAGAGAUGUUCUAGAAGUACUAUUAGAAGGAACACACAGAGAGCCUGACACAGUGGCUCACAUCUGUAAUCCCAGCAAUGCAGGAGGAUUCCUUGAACCCAGGAGUUUAAGGCUGAAGUGAGCUAUAAUUGCACCACUGCACCGUAGCUUGGGCAAGAGAGCAACACCCUGUUUAUUAAAAACAAAAACCAAAAAAGAAAGGUAGCACACAGAAACUCACAAUGACAGAAGUUGGGGUCACCUACCCCAGAUGUUUCCAGUGAGGCUGCUUGCAGGAAUUACCUGGGGGUUAUUUUCAUUGGUAAAAUCAGACUUUUGGGGGGCAGGACUAAAAAAUCUGGAUUUGUAAUUAAUCAAGUUCAUUUUGAUGAGAAAUAAACUUUUGAAGCCAUUAAUCAGUUUCCUUAGGACUCGCAGGACAGAUGGGACACUCUGCUGUUUCUUUUCUUCUUUCUUUUCUUUGAGACAGAGUCUCACUCUGUUACCCAGGCUGGAGUGCAGUGACACAAUCUCAACUCACUGCAACAUCCGCCUCCCAGGUUCAAGUUAUUCUCCUGCCUCAGCCUCCUAAGUAGCUGGGAUUACAGGCGGGCACCACCAUGCCCUGCUAGUUUUUGUAUUUUUGGUAGAGAUGGGGUUUCACCAUGUUGGCCAGGCUGGUCUCGAACUCCUGACCUCAAGUGAUCUGCCCACCUUGGCCUCCCAAAGUGCUGGGAUUACAGGCAUGAGCCACUAUACUCAACCACUUUGCUGUUUCUUAUGAUUGUAAUAGACAUCCUUCAAUGCGUCAUUAUGUGGUUGAACCCUUGGGAGUUACUACUUGAACCUGACCUACGGUCUUAAUGCAUCUUCACUGACUUCUUUCACUUCAUUCUUCAUUCAGCAUGACCAUCAUACCCUCUUGGAAGACAACCACUCCCUCCUUCAGCCUUUCAAUUCAAACCUUUCCCACAAUGCAUGUAACUAUAGGUUCUAGUCUCAUCAUCAUCAUCAUUAUAGCACCUCAUUUUCAUGGAUUAAUGCUAAUCCCAGUGUUCUAGAGGCUAUCUCUUGAGAUUGUUGCAUACUGGGUUUCCUAUUGGAUGCCCUCCUGCAAUUCAAGGGAGACUCACUCAGAAAGCUCCGCAGAUCAGAAAAUCAGUAGAUCCUCUUAGCUGACCCUUGACCUCCAUACUAUUUCCUGAGGUUGAUUCUUUCACCAUCUCUCUGCCUCUGCAGCAACAGCAGAAAUAGCUAAAGACUAAAGAAUUAACAAAAAGAAGGCAGCCAUUUAAUUGAUGCUUCUGAUGUGAAGCAUUCUUGAUUAUUUCAGGAAGAGAGUUUUUAUAGAGUCAAACCUUUAUUUACCUACAGACAACCUAAGGCAGUAUCCUUUUCCCACCGAUCUUUCAUUUUUACAUUCCUUCCUCCUCCAACCCCUUCCUCAGUCAGAUUGAGCCACUUUGGACCAAUGAGGCUCAAAACAAGCUCAAAGAGUCAAGAUUUUAAAGAUCAAAAAUUUAAACAAAUUAUCUGGCAUCCUACCUCCUAGUUUUGAGCUUCCUUUUUUAACAGUUGGGCAACAUUGCUUAACUAGGUCCAGUUUUGCUCAGAGCAAAAGGAUGGAGGCAGCUGCAUAGGCCUGAGAAAACUGCAGUUGUGAGGCCUAGUCUUCAUGGUUUCCCAAGCUCUUUGGGCUUCCAACUGCCUUAAAAGUAGCUCAUACCUGGCCGUGUGCGGUGGCUCGUGCCUGUAAUCCCAGCACUUUGGGAGGCCAAGGCGGGCAGAUCACGAGGUCAGGAGAUCGAGACCGUCCUGGCUAACACAGUGAAACCCUGACUCUACUAAAAAUACAAAAAAUUAGCUGGGUGUGUUGGCACGUGCCUGUAGUCCCAGCUACUUGGGAGGCUGAGGCAGGAGAAUCCCUUGAACCCAGGAGAGGGAGGUUGCAGUGAGCCGAGAUCACGCCACUGCACUCCAGCCUGGGCGACAGAGCAAGACUCCAUCUCAAAAAAAAAAAAAAAAAAAAAAAGUAGCUCAUGCUCAUAUCUCACCCCUUUGGAAGAUAUCCAUUAUUCUGUUCCUGAUUUGGUAGAAAGAGAAAGGGUGGAAAGUCAAGCAGUUCUUACUAUUUGAGAGUUACUACCCGUGUGCUCUUGAGCCUGUUGCUUAAUCUCCCAAAAAUCCCAGCAUGUGUGUGUGUGGGGGGGGGUGUGGGUGUGUGAGAGACAGAGAGAGAGAGAGAGAGAGAGAAAUUGGCAUAAUUAUUCCUACCUCAUCAGAUUAUUGUGCAUAUCAAUGUGGUCCAUGAUACAAAGCACCUAGCAGUAUCUGGCUCAAAAAAAGGAUUUAGUGUCGCUUCCCUUCCCAUCUUGAGCUCUGUUUGGCAGGUCGUUGGUUAAUCAGCAUAAAUUGCAAAGUGCUAGGACUUAAAAGAUCCUAUCUCUGAAUAUAUAUCCAUACUUGCUACUCCAGAGUACAGCAUAACAAUAAGAAUGUAAAUGAUCAUGAGCAACUUAGUUAAUCACUCAAAAGCUUCAGUUUCUUCAUUCUUAAAAUGAUGGUUUUAUGUGAAUGACCUCCGAAGGUCCCCCCACUGUUUGCUUCACUGGUUUUAAACUAGAGAUAAACCAGCCCUCUGAAGUUUUUACAAUGCAACAAGGGUUGCUGCAGCUGUUUCUUAGGUUAUAAUCAUAGAAAAUAGCCCAGUAAUUCAGAAAGACAAGAAAGUAUUUAAGAAUAAAUGGCAGGAGUCCUAACAAUUACAAUCAGGUAGAAAGAUACAGAGAAGACAGAUAAUGUUAAAUUACAACUGAAAUGCAGGUGGCAAUUACAGCAACAAAAGUAAUACCAGCACAAGAGGCUAACAGCAGGUUCUGCGUUAUACAACAAAAUGUCCUUUCCAAGGGUUUUUUUUUUAAUAAUUGCACUUCUGCUAGAUUUGUAAUUACAAACAUGAAUAAUCCUCAGCAUAUAUCAUUUCUAAAGAUAGAGGCUGUAAUUCUGUUCCUGAUGAAGAGCUGAAGAAUAUCUCACACCGGUUGGUAAGUGACAGUCAGUAACUACCAGACAAUUAGGAUGAUGCAUCAGGAAAAUUGGAGUCAAAAUAUCCCAUGUACAGAUGCUGAGUCCAUCAACAAAGGAGGGAUAUCGUCAUCACAUCUAGCAGCAGAAGACACAGGAAAACCACAUCACAACAAGGAUAAAGGGCAAUGGCGUUGCUGCAGAGGACAGAACGGUCAUCACUUCGGUCCUACCUGAGUUAACUCUCAAAGACUAUGGAAAAUAACUUUAUUCUUAAAAGGCAGCCAAGGAAAAUAUUUUAAGUAGGGGGAUGUGAUUAAUGGAACAUGUAGAGCCCUCAAUAUCAAAUUACUGGUUUGCGUGUGAACCCUGUGUUUGGGUUGGACUUCUCCAUGGUAUGUAACAUUCAUGAGUUGUAAAUAGCUGAUAAUCAAGUCAGGUAAAUUUGAGAGUUAAUGAUUUAGGUUGCUUUCAGCUGGAGUCAUCCUUGACUCCUUGCUUUUCUCCCACAUUCCCCUAUACUCAGGAAAUCCUGUUGGCUCUGCCUUCAGAACAUAUCCAGAAUCCAAACCACUGCUCACCACCUUCAUCACUACAACCCUGGACCACUGCUGCAGCAUCUCCAGCCUGGCAUGGGACUGUGGCCUUCUAAGUCAGCUCCCUGCACCUUCCUUUACUGCUCCAAAAUCCUUUCCCAACACAGUAGCUAGAGUGAUCUUUUUCACUCUACUCAAAAGCCUUCUGUGGUUCCCCAUUUGAAUCAGAGUCAAAGCCAAACAAAAUGCUUCUGCAC